AGAUUGCGAUAAGCCCUCUUCCAGGCUGCACUAAACUCAAGCCUCUAUCCUGCUGGAUUCUGAGCUCCCCUUCCUAAGACAGAGGGGUCCACCCGGAUACACCCGCAUUCUGAAGCACUUCCCGAGAUCGGCGCCUAAGCAAGAGAAGCAGGACGACUAUGGCGGCUCAGCCGAGGGGCGGGGACUACAGAGGAUUCUUCCUGCUCUCCAUCCUCCUGGGGACCCCCUGGGAAGCCUGGGCAGGACGUAUUCUCUACUCCGUGUCGGAGGAGACGGACAAAGGGUCCUUUGUGGGAGACAUCGCCAAGGACCUGGGGCUGGAGCCCCGGGAGCUGGCGGAGCGCGGAGUCCGCAUCAUCUCCAGAGGUAGGACGCAGCUUUUCGCCCUGAACCAGCGCAGCGGCAGCUUGGUCACUGCGGGCAGGAUAGACCGGGAAGAGAUCUGCGCUCAGAGUGCGCGGUGUCUGGUAAACUUUAACAUCCUGAUGGAAGAUAAAAUGAAUCUUUACCCUAUAGACGUGGAAAUAAUAGAUAUUAAUGACAACGUUCCAAGAUUCUUGACGGAAGAAAUAAAUGUAAAAAUAAUGGAGAAUACAGCUCCUGGGGUUCGGUUUCCGUUAAGCGAGGCUGGGGAUCCAGAUGUGGGCACGAACUCCCUCCAGAGUUACCAGCUCAGCCCCAAUCGCCACUUCUCCCUGGCUGUGCAAAGUGGAGACGAUGAAACUAAGUACCCGGAACUGGUGCUGGAGCGGGUGCUGGACCGGGAGGAAGAGCGGGUUCACCACCUGGUCCUCACAGCCUCUGAUGGCGGCGACCCGCCCCGAUCCAGCACCGCCCACAUCCAGGUGACAGUGGUGGAUGUGAAUGACCACACGCCUGUCUUCUCUCUGCCUCAGUACCAAGUAACUGUCCCCGAGAAUGUGCCAGUGGGUACAAGACUGCUCACGGUACAUGCUAUCGACCUGGACGAGGGAGUCAAUGGGGAAGUGACAUAUUCUUUUCGGAAAAUAACUCCUAAACUUCCAAAGAUGUUUCAUCUGAACUCGCUUACAGGAGAAAUAUCAACUUUAGAAGGAUUAGAUUAUGAAGAAACUGCCUUCUAUGAAAUGGAGGUUCAGGCUCAAGAUGGUCCUGGUAGUCUGACAAAGGCAAAAGUACUGAUCACAGUUUUAGAUGUAAAUGAUAAUGCUCCAGAAGUGACUAUGACGUCUUUAAGUAGCUCAAUCCCUGAAGACACACCUCUUGGGACAGUCAUUGCUCUUUUCUACCUACAAGACAGAGAUUCUGGAAAGAAUGGUGAGGUGACCUGCACCAUUCCAGAAAACCUACCUUUUAAAUUAGAAAAAUCAAUAGAUAAUUAUUAUAGAUUGGUCACAACCAAAAACUUGGACCGGGAAACACUCUCUUUGUAUAACAUCACACUGAAAGCCACAGAUGGUGGAACUCCUCCCUUGUCCAGGGAAACUCACAUAUUCAUGCAGGUGGCAGACACCAACGAUAACCCACCCACCUUCCCCCACUCAUCCUACUCAGUCUACAUCGCUGAGAACAACCCCAGAGGGGCCUCCAUUUUCUUAGUGACUGCACAGGACCACGACAGUGAGGAUAAUGCCCAGAUCACUUAUUCCUUGGCCGAAGACACCAUCCAGGGGGCUCCAGUGUCCUCCUAUGUCUCCAUAAACUCUGACACUGGAGUCCUGUACGCGCUGCAAUCCUUUGAUUAUGAGCAGUUGAGAGAACUACAACUAAGAGUGACUGCACAUGACAGCGGGGACCCGCCUCUCAGCAGCAACAUGUCACUGAGCCUGUUCGUGCUGGACCAGAAUGACAACCCGCCCGAGAUCCUGUACCCGGCCCUCCCCACAGAUGGUUCUACUGGCAUGGAGCUGGCACCCCGCUCCGCAGAGCCCGGCUACCUGGUGACCAAGGUGGUGGCGGUGGACAAAGAUUCAGGCCAGAACGCCUGGCUGUCAUACCUCCUGCUUAAGGCCAGCGAGCCAGGACUCUUUGCGGUUGGGCUGUACACGGGCGAGGUGCGCACGGCUCGGGCCCUGCUGGACAGAGAUGCCCUCAAGCAGAGCCUCGUGGUGGCCGUCCAGGACCACGGUCAGCCUCCUCUGUCAGCCACCGUCACACUCACCGUGGCUGUGGCUGACAGCAUCCCCGAAGUCUUGGCCGACCUGGGCAGCCUUGAGCCCUCCGACGGUCCUUACAACUAUGACCUCACGUUGUACCUGGUGGUGGCGGUGGCCACAGUCUCCUGCGUCUUCCUAGCCUUCGUCCUCGUACUGCUGGCGCUCAGGCUGCGGCGCUGGCACAAGUCACGCCUGCUGCAGGCUUCAGAAGGUGGCUUGGCGAACGUGCCCACCUCGCACUUUGUGGGCAUGGACGGGGUGCAGGCUUUCCUGCAGACCUAUUCCCAUGAGGUCUCCCUCACCGCGGACUCUCGGAAGAGUCACCUGAUCUUCCCCCAGCCCAACUAUGUAGACAUGCUCAUCAGCCAGGAGAGCUGUGAGAAAAAUGAUUCUUUGCUAACAUCCGUAGAUUUUCAGGAAUGUAAAGAAAACCUGCCAAGUAUUCAGCAAGCCCCGCCCAACACGGACUGGCGUUUCUCUCAGGCCCAGAGACCCGGCACCAGCGGCUCCCAAAAUGGCGAUGACACCGGCACCUGGCCCAACAACCAGUUUGACACAGAGAUGCUGCAAGCCAUGAUCUUGGCGUCCGCCAGUGAAGCUGCUGAUGGGAGCUCCACCCUGGGAGGGGGUGCCGGCACCAUGGGAUUGAGCGCCCGCUACGGACCCCAGUUCACCCUGCAGCACGUGCCCGACUACCGCCAGAAUGUCUACAUCCCAGGCAGCAAUGCCACACUGACCAACGCAGCUGGCAAGCGGGAUGGCAAGGCCCCAGCAGGUGGCAAUGGCAACAAGAAGAAGUCGGGCAAGAAGGAGAAGAAGUAACAUGGAGGCCAGGCCAAGAGCCACAGGGCGGCCUCUCCCCAACCAGCCCAGCUUCUCCUUACCUGCACCCAGGCCUCAGAGUUUCAGGGCUAACCCCCAGAAUACUGGUAGGGGCCAAGGCCAUGCUCCCCUUGGGAAACAGAAACAAGUGCCCAGUCAGCACCUACCCCUUCCCCCCCAGGGGGUUGAAUAUGCAAAAGCAGUUCCGCUGGGAACCCCCAUCCAAUCAACUGCUGUACCCAUGGGGGUAGUGGGGUUACUGUAGACACCAAGAACCAUUUGCCACACCCCGUUUAGUUACAGCUGAACUCCUCCAUCUUCCAAAUCAAUCAGGCCCAUCCAUCCCAUGCCUCCCUCCUCCCCACCCCACUCCAACAGUUCCUCUUUCCCGAGUAAGGUGGUUGGGGUGUUGAAGUACCAAGUAACCUACAAGCCUCCUAGUUCUGAAAAGUUGGAAGGGCAUCAUGACCUCUUGGCCUCUCCUUUGAUUCUCAAUCUUCCCCCAAAGCAUGGUUUGGUGCCAGCCCCUUCACCUCCUUCCAGAGCCCAAGAUCAAUGCUCAAGUUUUGGAGGACAUGAUCACCAUCCCCAUGGUACUGAUGCUUGCUGGAUUUAGGGAGGGCAUUUUGCUACCAAGCCUCUUCCCAACGCCCUGGGGACCAGUCUUCUGUUUUGUUUUUCAUUGUUUGACGUUUCCACUGCAUGCCUUGACUUCCCCCACCUCCUCCUCAAACAAGAGACUCCACUGCAUGUUCCAAGACAGUAUGGGGUGGUAAGAUAAGGAAGGGAAGUGUGUGGAUGUGGAUGGUGGGGGCAUGGACAAAGCUUGACACAUCAAGUUAUCAAGGCCUUGGAGGAGGCUCUGUAUGUCCUCAGGGGACUGACAACAUCCUCCAGAUUCCAGCCAUAAACCAAUAACUAGGCUGGACCCUUCCCACUACAUAAUAGGGCUCAGCCCAGGCAGCCAGCUUUGGGCUGAGCUAACAGGACCAAUGGAUUAAACUGGCAUUUCAGUCCAAGGAAGCUCGAAGCAGGUUUAGGACCAGGUCCCCUUGAGAGGUCAGAGGGGCCUCUGUGGGUGCUGGGUACUCCAGAGGUGCCACUGGUGGAAGGGUCAGCGGAGCCCCAGCAGGAAGGGUGGGCCAGCCAGGCCAUUCUUAGUCCCUGGGUUGGGGAGGCAGGGAGCUAGGGCAGGGACCAAAUGAACAGAAAGUCUCAGCCCAGGAUGGGGCUUCUUCAACAGGGCCCCUGCCCUCCUGAAGCCUCAGUCCUUCACCUUGCCAGGUGCCGUUUCUCUUCCGUGAAGGCCACUGCCCAGGUCCCCAGUGCGCCCCCUAGUGGCCAUAGCCUGGUUAAAGUUCCCCAGUGCCUCCUUGUGCAUAGACCUUCUUCUCCCACCCCCUUCUGCCCCUGGGUCCCCGGCCAUCCAGCGGGGCUGCCAGAGAACCCCAGACCUGCCCUUACAGUAGUGUAGCGCCCCCUCCCUCUUUCGGCUGGUGUAGAAUAGCCAGUAGUGUAGUGCGGUGUGCUUUUACGUGAUGGCGGGUGGGCAGCGGGCGGCGGGCUCCGCGCAGCCGUCUGUCCUUGAUCUGCCCGCGGCGGCCCGUGUUGUGUUUUGUGCUGUGUCCACGCGCUAAGGCGACCCCCUCCCCCGUACUGACUUCUCCUAUAAGCGCUUCUCUUCGCAUAGUCACGUAGCUCCCACCCCACCCUCUUCCUGUGUCUCACGCAAGUUUUAUACUCUAAUAUUUAUAUGGCUUUUUUUCUUCGACAAAAAAAUAAUAAAACGUUUCUUCUGAAAA